GUAGCUGAGAGACGACCUGGAAGUUCUGAGGCAGCCUUUGUCUGGCUGGAACACGCAUUGGCAGCGGGAGCUGUCGGUAGGACCUGGGACACCGCGGAAGUCGGGAAAUGGCCUCAGUGGCUUUAGAGGAUGUGGCUGUGAACUUCACCCGAGAAGAGUGGGCUUUGCUGGGUCCUUGUCAGAAGAAUCUCUACAAAGAUGUGAUGCAGGAAACCAUCAGGAACCUGGAUUGUGUAGUAAUGAAAUGGAAAGACCAGAACAUUGAAGAUCAAUAUAGAUAUCCCAGGAAAAAUCUAAGAUGUCGUAUGUUAGAGAGAUUUGUUGAAAGUAAAGAUGGAACUCAAUGUGGAGAAACAUCUAGCCAGAUUCAAGAUAGUAUUGUGACCAAGAACACUCUUCCUGGAGUAGGUCCUUGUGAAAGCAGUAUGAGAGGAGAAAAAGUCAUGGGUCAUUCAUCCCUUAAUUGUUACAUCAGAGUUGGUGCUGGGCACAAACCACAUGAGUAUCAUGAAUGUGGAGAGAAGCCAGAUACGCAUAAACAACGUGGGAAAGCCUUCAGUUACCACAACUCAUUUCAAACACAUGAGAGGCUUCACACUGGAAAGAAACCAUAUGAUUGUAAAGAAUGUGGGAAGUCCUUCAGUUCUUUGGGAAACCUUCAAAGACACAUGGCAGUGCAGCGUGGAGAUGGACCUUAUAAAUGUAAGUUGUGUGGGAAAGCGUUUUUUUGGCCCAGUUUAUUACAUAUGCAUGAAAGAACGCACACUGGAGAGAAACCAUAUGAAUGUAAGCAGUGUUCUAAAGCCUUUUCUUUUUACAGUUCCUAUCUAAGACAUGAAAGAACACAUACUGGGGAGAAACCGUAUGAAUGUAAACAGUGUUCUAAAGCCUUUCCUUUUUACAGUUCCUAUCUAAGACAUGAAAGAACACAUACUGGGGAGAAACCAUAUAAAUGUAAGCAGUGUUCUAAAGCCUUCCCUGAUUCCAGUUCUUGUCUAAUACAUGAAAGAACUCACACUGGAGAGAAACCCUAUACAUGUAAACAAUGUGGGAAAGCCUUCAGUGUUUCCGGUUCCCUUCAAAGACAUGAAACCACUCACAGUGCAGAGAAACCCUAUGCAUGUCAGCAAUGUGGGAAAGCGUUUCAUCAUCUGGGAAGCUUUCAAAGACACAUGAUAAGGCACACUGGAAAUGGACCUCAUAAAUGUAAGAUAUGUGGGAAAGGCUUUGAUUGUCCUAGUUCACUGCAAAGUCAUGAAAGAACUCACACUGGAGAGAAACCCUAUGAAUGCAAGCAGUGUGGGAAAGCAUUAUCUCAUCGCUCAAGCUUUCGAAGUCAUAUGAUAAUGCACACUGGAGAUGGACCUCAUAAAUGCAAGGUAUGUGGGAAAGCCUUUGUUUAUCCCAGUGUAUUUCAAAGACAUGAAAGGACUCACACUGCAGAGAAACCCUAUAAAUGUAAACAAUGUGGCAAAGCCUACCGUAUUUCCAGUUCCCUUCGAAGGCAUGAAACAACUCAUACUGGAGAGAAACCCUAUAAAUGCAAACUUGGGAAAGCCUGUAUUGAUUUCUGUUCCUUUCAAAAUCACAAAACAACUCACACUGGAGAGAAGCCAUAUGAGUGUAAGGAAUGUGGGAAAGCAUUCAGUCGUUUCAGAUACCUUUCUCGACAUAAAAGGACUCACACAGGAGAGAAACCUUAUGAGUGUAAAACAUGUAGGAAAGCCUUCGGUCAUUAUGAUAACUUAAAGGUACAUGAAAGAAUUCACUCUGGAGAGAAGCCGUAUGAAUGUAAGGAAUGUGGGAAAGCAUUCUCUUGGCUCACUUGCUUUCUACGACAUGAAAGAAUUCACAUGAGAGAGAAAUCCUAUGAAUGUCCACAAUGUGGUAAAGCCUUCACUCAUUCCCGUUUUCUUCAAGGACAUGAAAAAACUCAUACUGGAGAGAACCCGUAUGAAUGUAAGGAAUGUGGGAAAGCAUUUGCUUCUCUCAGUUCCUUGCAUAGACAUAAAAAGACUCACUGGAAAAAAACUCACACUGGAGAGAACCCAUAUGAAUGUAAGGAAUGUGGGAAAGCAUUUGCUUCUCUCAGUUCCUUGCAUAGACAUAAAAAGACUCACUAGCAUUCUCUCUAAAUGUAUGGAAUGUGGGAAAGCAUUUAUUAAUUUUAUUUCAUUUCAGAUACUUGUACGAAACACAUUGGAGAUAGACCCUGUGAAUGUAAGCACUUGGUAAAGCCUUAAGUAGUUUCAGUUUCUUUCCAGUACAGUCAUCCCUUGAUACCUGCUGGGUAUUGGUUCCAGCACUCCGUGAGCCAUGUCCAGUCCCUUUUAUAAAAUGACAUGUUUGUAUGUAACUUACCCACAUCCUCUUGUAUAGUCUCAAUUAUGUCUAGAUUACUUAAAAUACCUCAUGCAUUAUAAAAGCUAUGCAAAUAGUUGUUCUAUUGUAUUGUUUAGGGAAUCAUGAUAAGGAAAAGAGUCUAUGUAUUUUCAGUAUAGAUGCAGUAAUUGUGAGCCUAUCAACAUAGUGUAGUCAGCCAGAACAUUAAAGUUUCUUUGUUUCAACUCUCA